CUUGCAGAGCCGGCGCCGGAGGAGACGCACGCAGCUGACUUUGUCUUCUCCGCACGACUGUUACAGAGGUCUCCAGAGCCUUCUCUCUCCUGGUAGGUUUCGGCUCAGGACCCUGAAUCCUGGCCCACAGGCAAGCCUGAUGGGACGUGCGGGGUAGUACUUGUAUGGGGAGACGCGGGAAGGAGGAAGAAGCACAUCUGUCCUCCGCGGCCUUUAGCUCUGAGCAUCCGGCCGCGGGCCCUGACUUUGCCGCUCAGUUUGGGGCGCAGGGGGGGCCGUGCCCUGGCGGAGGAGCAGAAGGCAGAGGGUAGCAGCUGCGGCUCAGCGGAGAGACUUGUUGCAUUUGCAGCUAAAACCAGGCCCUACUUGUCCUUGUGCAAAAUGGCAACUCUUAAGGAAAAACUCAUUGCACCAGUUGCGGAAGAAGAGGCAACAGUUCCAAACAAUAAGAUCACUGUAGUGGGUGUUGGACAAGUUGGUAUGGCGUGUGCUAUCAGCAUUCUGGGAAAGUCUCUGGCUGAUGAACUUGCUCUUGUGGAUGUUUUGGAAGAUAAGCUUAAAGGAGAAAUGAUGGAUCUGCAGCAUGGGAGCUUAUUUCUUCAGACACCUAAAAUUGUGGCAGAUAAAGAUUAUUCUGUGACUGCCAAUUCUAAGAUUGUAGUGGUAACUGCAGGAGUCCGUCAGCAAGAAGGGGAGAGUCGGCUCAAUCUGGUGCAGAGAAAUGUUAAUGUCUUCAAAUUCAUUAUUCCUCAGAUCGUCAAGUACAGUCCUGAUUGCAUCAUAAUUGUGGUUUCCAACCCAGUGGACAUUCUUACGUAUGUUACCUGGAAACUAAGUGGAUUACCCAAACACCGCGUGAUUGGAAGUGGAUGUAAUCUGGAUUCUGCUAGAUUUCGCUACCUUAUGGCUGAAAAACUUGGCAUUCAUCCCAGCAGCUGCCAUGGAUGGAUUUUGGGGGAACAUGGCGACUCAAGUGUGGCUGUGUGGAGUGGUGUGAAUGUGGCAGGUGUUUCUCUCCAGGAAUUGAAUCCAGAAAUGGGAACUGACAAUGAUAGUGAAAAUUGGAAGGAAGUGCAUAAGAUGGUGGUUGAAAGUGCCUAUGAAGUCAUCAAGCUAAAAGGAUAUACCAACUGGGCUAUUGGAUUAAGUGUGGCUGAUCUUAUUGAAUCCAUGUUGAAAAAUCUAUCCAGGAUUCAUCCCGUGUCAACAAUGGUAAAGGGGAUGUAUGGCAUUGAGAAUGAAGUCUUCCUGAGCCUUCCAUGUAUCCUCAAUGCCCGGGGAUUAACCAGCGUUAUCAACCAGAAGCUAAAGGAUGAUGAGGUUGCUCAGCUCAAGAAAAGUGCAGAUACCCUGUGGGACAUCCAGAAGGACCUAAAAGACCUGUGACUAGUGAGCUCUAGGCUGUAGAAAUUUAAAAACUACAAUGUGAUUAACUCGAGCCUUUAGUUUUCAUCCAUGUACAUGGAUCACAGUUUGCUUUGAUCUUCUUCAAUAUGUGAAUUUGGGCUCACAGAAUCAAAGCCUAUGCUUGGUUUAAUGCUUGCAAUCUGAGCUCUUGAACAAAUAAAAUUAACUAUUGUAGUGUG